ACUCGGCGUCCAGUCUCUUAGCAACGACUCCGGCUUCCUAGGAACUGCUCCUUUCUCAACCAUUCCUGCCCACAACACCCCAGCUUGCUGCCAGCAAAGCCCCUCCACACCCCUCAAACUCCAGACCCUUCACAUCAAUUUACUGUUUUCUUCGACCUCACCCCAGCAAUUUUCUCUGAAUCAACCCCCUUUCCUCCUCUCCUAAGUCUCUGAGUUUCUCUCUCCUCCUGCCAUCCUGAGUUCUGCCAUCCUUAGGGGCCGCCAAGACCUCUCUUUUCGUUCCUCUCCCGCCUCAGACCAGCAGCCUUUUAUUUUAGAUCAUGUCUGGAGGGAAGUCAGCCCAGGGUCCAGAGGAAGGGGGCGUCUGCAUCACUGAAGCCCUUAUCACUAAGCGGAACUUGACUUUCCCUGAAGAUGGGGAACUGUCAGAGAAGAUGUUUCACACUCUUGAUGAACUGCAGACUGUCCGCCUGGACCGGGAGGGGAUUACUACUAUCAGGAACUUAGAAGGCCUCCAGAAUCUUCACAGUCUCUAUCUGCAAGGGAAUAAGAUCCAGCAAAUUGAGAACCUGGCUUGCAUCCCCUCCUUGCGCUUCCUGUCUCUGGCAGGAAACCAAAUCAGGCAGGUGGAAAACCUCCUCGACCUCCCAUGCCUCCAGUUUCUGGACCUUUCUGAGAACCUGAUAGAAACAUUGAAGCUGGAUGAGUUCCCCCAGAGCCUUCUCAUCCUCAACCUGUCUGGAAACAGCUGCACCAACCAGGAUGGCUACCGCGAGCUGGUGACAGAAGCCCUGCCACUUCUCCUGGACCUGGACGGGCAGCCUGUGGUGGAGCGCUGGAUUUCGGAUGAGGAGGAUGAAGCCUCAAGCGAUGAGGAGUUCCCAGAGCUGAGUGGCCCAUUCUGCUCAGAACGAGGCUUCCUCAAGGAGCUGGAGCAGGAGCUGAGCAGGCACAGGGAGCACCGGCAACAGACGGCCCUGACAGAGCACCUGCUGAGGAUGGAGAUGCAGCCCACCCUCACCGACCUGCCCCUGCUACCUGGGGUGCCCAUGGCUGGGGACAGCAGCCCUUCUGCCACUCCUGCGCAAGGGGAGGAGACAGUCCCUGAGGCCGUCUCCUCACCCCAGGCCUCCUCUCCCACCAAGAAACCAUGCAGUCUGAUUCCCAGGGGCCACCAAAGCUCUUUCUGGGGAAGGAAGGGGGCACGAGCAGCCACAGCCCCCAAGGCCUCUGUGGCUGAGGCCCCCAGCACAACCAAAACUACGGCCAAGAGAAGCAAGAAAUGAUUCUCUGUCAACCUUUCUCUACUAGUGGAGAGGAGUGGGGCCUGCCCCUCUUCUCAGACCUCUGACCUGUGACAGAAGCCCAUCCCCAGUAAAGUGUCUCUAGGCCCUGAGUAUGCUUUUCAUGUCACUUGGGGUAUCUCAGGGGAAGAAACCAGUGAAAGCUCCAGGAAACAAAAUACAGAGCUCAGUGAGCCACCUGAUUCUAAAGAGCGAGUCUGGAAUCUUUCGGGAGCUACCCACAGGGCAGGCAUGCCUCAGGCCCCCGCUGGCUUCCUGGCUCCCACUUGGGCAGGAAGCGGGCACCACCUCAUGGAAGAGGCAUGCCAUCUCACUGCCACCCCUAGCGAGUGCCCUUCCCCGGUCCAAGCCAAGGACCAAGGAGCUGUGGUCCUAGUCAUCCCCAACAGCAGCCAGCUCCUGUCCCCUCCCUGUCCUCCUGCCCAGUCCCCAUCACUCACCCACUCAUAGGAAUGAGUACACAACCACAGGCCCCGCAGCCAGCCCACAGCUGCCUUUGGGCCUCACUUGGCUCUCCCACCCCCACUGGUCCUGGGAUAAAGUUCACUGAAGAGAAAAUAAAGCACAUUUAUUAAGGCAAA